ACUCUGAAGCCAAGAGCCGACCUUCUGAGCCCUCAAGAAAGAUCAGAACAGAUUCAUGGGUGAUUUAGCCUAUCUGUCCCAGGCCAGCGUGGCUGAGUGUGCUGGCUGGAGGCCUCUCUCUCUGCUUCGAGGGUAGCUGAGAUCCACCCCGGAAACCGGCAGGAUGAAGGGGGCAAGUGAGGAGAAGCUGGCAUCUGUGUCCAACCUGGUCACUGUGUUUGAGAAUAGCAGGACCCCAGAAGCAGCACCCAGAGGCCAGAGGCUAGAGGACGUGCAUCACCGCCCUGAGUGCAGGCCUCCCGAGUCCCCAGGACCACGGGAGAAGACGAAUGUCGGGGAGGCCGUGGGGUCUGAGCCCAGGACAGUCAGCAGGAGGUACCUGAACUCCCUGAAGAACAAGCUGUCCAGCGAAGCCUGGAGGAAAUCUUGCCAGCCUGUGACCCUCUCAGGAUCGGGGACGCAGGAGCCAGAGAAGAAGAUCGUCCAGGAGCUGCUGGAGACAGAGCAGGCCUAUGUGGCGCGCCUCCACCUGCUAGACCAGGUGUUUUUCCAGGAGCUGCUGAAGACAGCCCGCAGCAGCAAGGCCUUCCCAGAGGAUGUGGUCAGGGUCAUCUUCUCCAACAUCUCCUCCAUCUAUCAGUUCCAUUCUCAGUUCUUCCUCCCAGAGCUGCAGCGGCGCCUGGACGACUGGACAGCUAACCCCCGCAUCGGUGACGUGAUCCAGAAGCUGGCCCCCUUCCUGAAGAUGUACAGUGAGUAUGUCAAGAACUUUGAGCGAGCGGCUGAGCUGCUGGCCACCUGGACCGACAAGUCUCCACUCUUCCAGGAGGUUCUCACUCGCAUCCAGAGCAGCGAGGCUUCGGGCAGCCUGACCCUGCAGCACCACAUGCUGGAACCAGUGCAGAGAAUUCCACGUUACGAGCUGCUGCUCAAGGAGUACAUCCAGAAGCUGCCAGCCCAGGCCCCAGACCAGGCCGAUGCCCAGAAAGCCCUGGACAUGAUCUUCUCAGCUGCCCAGCACUCCAAUGCAGCCAUCACUGAGAUGGAGCGGCUGCAGGACCUGUGGGAGGUGUACCAGCGCCUGGGCCUCGAGGACGACAUAGUAGACCCCUCUAACACCCUGCUCCGUGAGGGCCCGGUCCUCAAGAUCUCCUUCCGCCGCAACGACCCCAUGGAGCGCUACCUUUUCUUGUUCAACAACAUGCUGCUCUACUGUGUGCCCAGGGUGAUCCAGGUGGGCGCCCAGUUCCAGGUGAGGACCCGCAUCGAUGUGGCCGGGAUGAAGGCUUCAAUCCAGAGGGUUCAAGACUAUGGUGGAAUUUCUGGCAUCGUGGAGGACACAGCCAGAGAAGCUUCCUGACCACCCCUCUCUGCUGGCUCCUGAGUCCUGGUGUGUCCUGAGGGCUGGGACUGGAAGAAGCAGAGGUCUGGUCUGGCCCAUCUUGUCACUCUCCUAUUCAGCAUCACCCCUACCCCCUUCAGCCCCAGAAGGGAGCUGCAGGCAGGAGUUGAACCAGAAUGCUCUACCCUCUAGAGCCCCUGGGGCCUCCAGAGACCCCAGCAAAAGAGCCCCACCCCUGCUCCUGACUGGGGUUGCCUGGCAUCUGGAGCAAUCCAGGGCCUGGGGGUGGGGUGCAGCCUGGGAAUGAUGAAAGCUGAUGAGGGAACAUGGGUUCACAGCUCACCCCGACACCUGAGCUGACUGAAGUCUUUUAGGAGUGCAGCCCCGGCCCUGGCAUCUAGCUUUCCAUCCUGAAGGGGCCAGAAUGUCACAUAGACCAGGGCGUGUGCAGGCUUGUAUGUCUGGAGUCCUUGGUGAGUGAGGCUGAGAAAGGCAGGUUUAUAGAGAGCUACAGACAGAGAAAUGGAGACGGGUGGCCCUGCCAAAGGACUGUCAGAGACCCAGGCAUAGAAAAAUAGAGAUCGACAGAUAGGAAGGCUAAGAAAUAUAGAAACCAAAACAGAGUCAUAGAGAGAAAACAGAGAGAGCCGAGCCUGAGAGCAUCAGAUGCUUUGGGUGUGUGUUGAGAGCUCACCAGCCCUGUGUGUGCCGGGUCUCUGGAGUCUGCUAGUCUCGGCUAACAUGUCUGAUACUCCAGCAGCCGCACAGCACCCUCUCCUGGACGGCAUGGGCUUGGCAAGUGCAGAGCUGUCCACUCACCCUACUUCUGUGCAGGAACCAUUUUCUGAGUCUGUGAUUUGGAGGCAAAUCUUGCCUUUGACCAUCAUGAUGGUUCCUAUUGGCCUAUGACUCCCUGGCCUCCUCCUUCCUAGGUGUCAGGGAGGCCUAGUUCACAGCAGCUGAUUCUCUCCAAGGUCUGACUUGGUCUUAGUAUUUUGCCAUCCCCCACAGGGCCAGCCUGGGAAGAAGGAAGGGGUGUGGACACACAUACCUAGGGGCUCCACGUACAGUUGUGCAGGUUGUACACUGCACAAGGAUACCUCAUCUAAGAGGAUGUCUUCUGCAGCCAACUGCAGAUUAGCAGACUAUGAUAUAUCAUAGAUGGUAUAUUUAUAGUGAGAAUUGUCCGGCAGAUGGCAGUCAAAUGUCUUGUUCCAACAAUAUCUAGGUAUUAUGCCAGUUUGCCAACAGAUGUCAGUAAAGUGUUUUGAGGAAGGCUGUCCUUUUCUAAUUACUACAAACGUACUGUAUGGACUAGCAGGGGACUGAAUUGACCUAGCCCUGGGGAAAGUGGUUGAGGCUCAGCUCAGCACAGUUCUGGAAACUCCUCUUGAAACCUGCUGGGGAGCUGGAAGCCUCUGUAUGAACAUCCCAGGGGCAGCCUGGACCCUCAGGUCAGGAGCCCCCAGUUCCCUUUUUUCUGUCAAAAGCAUGAUAUUUCUUCCUGCUUCUGGACUGCAAACCUUGGAUUUCUCCCUUCUUUUCCCUUUCCCCUCUCCCUGACCCAGUUAGAAACCUCUUCUGUCUCUCCAGUGCACCUGGGCAGGCCAGGACCAUUUAUGAUGUUGCUUCCUAACUGGCCUUUGGGCUACAGGUUUGUCCCAUUUGGCCCACAUCCAGCCUGUCAUCCCUUGCACACAAAGAGGUAUUUGGCUCUUUCCCAAAUACCUCUUUCCACAUGACCGCCUCCUCAUUGCCAAGGGCAUCGAAUCCAAAUCACAUCAGCCCCUUCUAAGGCAAAGACUGGGGAGUGAGGCUGCAGACUAGGCCUAACCUGAGGAAAGAUGUGCUUGUACUCAGUGCUGUCUGGGUUAUGGUGAGCUGCCCUGGAAGUGUGCAAAGGCCUGGCCACCACAUGGGAGGCAGCAGAGGAGCUCAAGUGUUUGAGGAAUUUAAUGGCAACAAAGUUGCCCCACACAGAAGCUCUUGUGCUCUCAGCCUGUGUCUUAGGUUCUCUUUGCAAAUCUCUCUCCACACCGUCUGAAGGAAGUGUGCUUACAGGACUCUGGGGGUAGGAUGGAAAUAGAUGUUCUUCCAUCUCACCCUUGGGGGCUGAAAACCUGGGGUGGAAUCCUUCUUUUGCCCCUUAGGUGCUGUGUGACCUCAGGCAGCUCUCUUGCCCUCUCUGAGCAUCCAUUUCCUCAUCUCCUAAAUGAGGAUGAUAGUAUCUGCUUCCCAAGAUUGCUGUGAAGAUUAUUUUCUUCUUCUUUUCUUUUCUUUUCUUUUUUUUUUUUUUUGAGACAG